GUGCCACACUCACACAAGACCUGGAAUUGACAGGACUCCCAACUAGUACAAUGACAGAAGAUAAGGUCACUGGGACCCUGGUUUUCACUGUCAUCACUGCUGUGCUGGGUUCCUUCCAGUUUGGAUAUGACAUUGGUGUGAUCAAUGCACCUCAACAGGUAAUAAUAUCUCACUAUAGACAUGUUUUGGGUGUUCCACUGGAUGACCGAAAAGCUAUCAACAACUAUGUUAUCAACAGUACAGAUGAACUGCCCACAAUCUCAUACUCAAUGAACCCAAAACCAACCCCUUGGGCUGAGGAAGAGACUGUGGCAGCUGCUCAACUAAUCACCAUGCUCUGGUCCCUGUCUGUAUCCAGCUUUGCAGUUGGUGGAAUGACUGCAUCAUUCUUUGGUGGGUGGCUUGGGGACACACUUGGAAGAAUCAAAGCCAUGUUAGUAGCAAACAUUCUGUCAUUAGUUGGAGCUCUCUUGAUGGGGUUUUCAAAAUUGGGACCAUCUCAUAUACUUAUAAUUGCUGGAAGAAGCAUAUCAGGACUAUAUUGUGGGCUAAUUUCAGGCCUGGUUCCUAUGUAUAUCGGUGAAAUUGCUCCAACCGCUCUCAGGGGAGCACUUGGCACUUUUCAUCAGCUGGCCAUCGUCACGGGCAUUCUUAUUAGUCAGAUUAUUGGUCUUGAAUUUAUCUUGGGCAAUUAUGAUCUGUGGCACAUCCUGCUUGGCCUGUCUGGUGUGCGAGCCAUCCUUCAGUCUCUGCUACUCUUUUUCUGUCCAGAAAGCCCCAGAUACCUUUACAUCAAGUUAGAUGAGGAAGUCAAAGCAAAACAAAGCUUGAAAAGACUCAGAGGAUAUGAUGAUGUCACCAAAGAUAUUAAUGAAAUGAGAAAAGAAAGAGAAGAAGCAUCGAGUGAGCAGAAAGUCUCUAUAAUUCAGCUCUUCACCAAUUCCAGCUACCGACAGCCUAUUCUAGUGGCACUGAUGCUGCAUGUGGCUCAGCAAUUUUCCGGAAUCAAUGGCAUUUUUUACUACUCAACCAGCAUUUUUCAGACGGCUGGUAUCAGCAAACCUGUUUAUGCAACCAUUGGAGUUGGCGCUGUAAACAUGGUUUUCACUGCUGUCUCUGUAUUCCUUGUGGAGAAGGCAGGGCGACGUUCUCUCUUUCUAAUUGGAAUGAGUGGGAUGUUUGUUUGUGCCAUCUUCAUGUCAGUGGGACUUGUGCUGCUGAAUAAGUUCUCUUGGAUGAGUUAUGUGAGCAUGAUAGCCAUCUUCCUCUUUGUCAGCUUCUUUGAAAUUGGGCCAGGCCCGAUCCCCUGGUUCAUGGUGGCUGAGUUUUUCAGUCAAGGACCACGUCCUGCUGCUUUAGCAAUAGCUGCAUUCAGCAAUUGGACCUGCAAUUUCAUUGUAGCUCUGUGUUUCCAGUACAUUGCGGACUUCUGUGGACCUUAUGUGUUUUUCCUCUUUGCUGGAGUGCUCCUGGCCUUUACCCUGUUCACAUUUUUUAAAGUUCCAGAAACCAAAGGAAAGUCUUUUGAGGAAAUUGCUGCAGAAUUCCAAAAGAAGAGUGGCUCAGCCCACAGGCCAAAAGCUGCUGUAGAAAUGAAAUUCCUAGGAGCUACAGAGACUGUGUAAAAAAAAAACCCUGCUUUUUGACAUGAACAGAAACAAUAAGGGAACCGUCUGUUUUUAAAUGAUGAUUCCUUGAGCAUUUUAUAUCCACAUCUUUAAGUAUUGUUUUAUUUUUAUGUGCUCUCAUCAGAAAUGUCAUCAAAUAUUACCAAAAAAGUAUUUUUUUAAGUUAGAGAAUAUAUUUUUGAUGGUAAGACUGUAAUUAAGUAAACCAAAAAGGCUAGUUUAUUUUGUUACACUAAAGGGCAGGUGGUUCUAAUAUUUUUAGCUCUGUUCUUUAUAACAAGGUUCUUCUAAAAUUGAAGAGAUUUCAACAUAUCAUUUUUUUAACACAUAACUAGAAACCUGAGGAUGCAACAAAUAUUUAUAUAUUUGAAUAUCAUUAAAUUGGAAUUUUCUUACCCAUAUAUCUUAUGUUAAAGGAGAUAUGGCUAGUGGCAAUAAGUUCCAUGUUAAAAUAGACAACUCUUCCAUUUAUUGCACUCAGCUUUUUUCUUGAGUACUAGAAUUUGUAUUUUGCUUAAAAUUUUACUUUUGUUCUGUAUUUUCAUGUGGAAUGGAUUAUAGAGUAUACUAAAAAAUGUCUAUAGAGAAAAACUUUCAUUUUUGGUAGGCUUAUCAAAAUCUUUCAGCACUCAGAAAAGAAAACCAUUUUAGUUCCUUUAUUUAAUGGCCAAAUGGUUUUUGCAAGAUUUAACACUAAAAAGGUUUCACCUGAUCAUAUAGCGUGGGUUAUCAGUUAACAUUAACAUCUAUUAUAAAACCAUGUUGAUUCCCUUCUGGUACAAUCCUUUGAGUUAUAGUUUGCUUUGCUUUUUAAUUGAGGACAGCCUGGUUUUCACAUACACUCAAACAAUCAUGAGUCAGACAUUUGGUAUAUUACCUCAAAUUCCUAAUAAGUUUGAUCAAAUCUAAUGUAAGAAAAUUUGAAGUAAAGGAUUGAUCACUUUGUUAAAAAUAUUUUCUGAAUUAUUAUGUCUCAAAAUAAGUUGAAAAGGUAGGGUUUGAGGAUUCCUGAGUGUGGGCUUCUGAAACUUCAUAAAUGUUCAGCUUCAGACUUUUAUCAAAAUCCCUAUUUAAUUUUCCUGGAAAGACUGAUUGUUUUAUGGUGUGUUCCUAACAUAAAAUAAUCGUCUCCUUUGACAUUUCCUUCUUUGUCUUAGCUGUAUACAGAUUCUAGCCAAACUAUUCUAUGGCCAUUACUAACACGCAUUGUACACUAUCUAUCUGCCUUUACCUACAUAGGCAAAUUGGAAAUACACAGAUGAUUAAACAGACUUUAGCUUACAGUCAAUUUUACAAUUAUGGAAAUAUAGUUCUGAUGGGUCCCAAAAGCUUAGCAGGGUGCUAACGUAUCUCUAGGCUGUUUUCUCCACCAACUGGAGCACUGAUCAAUCCUUCUUAUGUUUGCUUUAAUGUGUAUUGAAGAAAAGCACUUUUUAAAAAGUACUCUUUAAGAGUGAAAUAAUUAAAAACCACUGAACAUUUGCUUUGUUUUCUAAAGUUGUUCACAUAUAUGUAAUUUAGCAGUCCAAAGAACAAGAAAUUGUUUCUUUUCA